AGUGCGCACGCGUGGCUGCAGCCCCGCCCCCGUUCCCCCGGCGCUCGGAGCCCGAGUCCGCGGGAAGAUGGCGGCGCCGCUCAUCCCCCUCUCCCAGCAGAUUCCCACUGGAAAUUCGUUGUAUGAAUCUUAUUACAAGCAGGUCGAUCCGGCAUACACAGGGAGGGUGGGGGCGAGUGAAGCUGCGCUUUUUCUAAAGAAGUCUGGCCUCUCGGACAUUAUCCUUGGGAAGAUAUGGGACUUGGCCGAUCCAGAAGGUAAAGGGUUCUUGGACAAACAGGGUUUCUAUGUUGCACUGAGACUGGUGGCCUGUGCACAGAGUGGCCAUGAAGUUACCUUGAGCAAUCUGAAUUUGAGCAUGCCACCGCCUAAAUUUCACGACACCAGCAGCCCUCUGAUGGUCACACCGCCCUCUGCAGAGGCCCACUGGGCUGUGAGGGUGGAAGAAAAGGCCAAAUUUGAUGGGAUUUUUGAAAGCCUCUUGCCCAUCAAUGGUUUGCUCUCUGGAGACAAAGUCAAGCCAGUCCUCAUGAACUCAAAGCUGCCUCUUGAUGUCCUGGGCAGGGUCUGGGACCUCAGUGACAUUGACAAGGAUGGGCACUUGGAUCGAGAUGAGUUCGCUGUGGCCAUGCACUUGGUGUACCGAGCCCUGGAGAAGGAGCCCGUGCCCUCCGCCCUGCCCCCGUCCCUCAUCCCACCCUCCAAGAGAAAGAAGACUGUGUUCCCUGGCGCCGUCCCCGUCCUGCCUGCCAGCCCCCCACCAAAAGACAGCCUCCGCUCCACGCCGUCCCACGGCAGCGUCAGCAGCCUCAACAGCACAGGGAGCCUGUCCCCCAAGCACAGCCUCAAGCAAACACAGCCAACAGUGAACUGGGUGGUGCCCGUGGCAGACAAGAUGCGAUUUGAUGAGAUAUUCCUGAAGACCGACCUGGACCUGGAUGGCUACGUGAGUGGCCAGGAGGUGAAGGAGAUCUUCAUGCACUCGGGCCUCACCCAGAACCUUCUAGCACACAUAUGGGCCCUGGCCGAUACGAGGCAAACGGGGAAGUUAAGCAAAGACCAAUUCGCGUUAGCUAUGUAUUUCAUUCAGCAGAAGGUCAGUAAAGGCAUCGACCCUCCUCAAGUCCUCUCGCCGGACAUGGUCCCGCCUUCGGAGAGAGGCACGCCCGGCCCGGACAGUUCAGGCUCUCUCGGCUCCGGGGAGUUUACUGGCGUGAAGGAGCUUGAUGACAUCAGUCAAGAGAUUGCCCAGUUACAAAGAGAGAAAUAUUCACUGGAACAAGACAUUCGAGAAAAGGAAGAGGCAAUCAGACAGAAAACCAGCGAGGUGCAGGAAUUACAAAAUGACCUAGACCGGGAAACAAGCAGUUUGCAGGAGCUCGAGGCUCAGAAACAGGAUGCUCAAGACCGCCUGGACGAGAUGGACCAGCAGAAGGCCAAGCUCCGAGACAUGCUGAGCGACGUCCGGCAGAAGUGCCAGGAUGAGACUCAGAUGAUCUCAUCACUGAAAACGCAAAUCCAAUCUCAGGAAUCUGACUUAAAGUCCCAGGAAGACGAUCUGAACCGAGCCAAGUCGGAGCUGAACCGAUUGCAGCAGGAGGAAACCCAGCUGGAGCAGAGCAUUCAGGCUGGGCGAGUCCAGCUGGAAACCAUCAUCAAGUCCCUGAAGUCAACGCAAGACGAAAUCAACCAGGCAAGGAGCAAACUUUCCCAGCUGCAUGAAAGCCGCCAGGAGGCCCACAGGAGCCUGGAGCAGUAUGACCAGGUGCUCGAUGGAGCCCAUGGUGCCAGCCUGACCGACCUGGCCAACCUGAGCGAAGGCGUCUCCCUGGCAGAGAGGGGCAGUUUUGGAGCCAUGGAUGAUCCUUUCAAAAAUAAAGCCUUGUUAUUUAGCAACAACACGCAAGAGUUGCAUCCGGAUCCUUUCCAGACAGAAGACCCCUUCAAAUCUGACCCAUUUAAAGGAGCUGACCCCUUCAAAGGCGACCCGUUCCAGAAUGACCCCUUUGCAGAACAGCAGACAACUUCAACAGAUCCAUUUGGAGGGGACCCUUUCAAAGAAAGUGACCCAUUCCGUGGCUCUGCCACUGACGACUUCUUCAAGAAACAGACAAAGAAUGACCCAUUUACCUCGGAUCCAUUCACGAAAAACCCUUCCUUACCUUCGAAGCUCGACCCCUUUGAAUCCAGUGAUCCCUUUUCAUCCUCCAGUGUCUCCUCAAAAGGAUCAGAUCCCUUUGGAACCUUAGAUCCCUUCGGAAGUGGGUCCUUCAAUAGUGCUGAAGGCUUUGCCGACUUCAGCCAGAUGUCCAAGGAAUGAAGGAAAGCAGAUGAGGUGUGUCCCGUCCCUGACACCUGCGUCCACUCUGUCCCUUCUCGGCAGCCCCCAGGCAGGGGCAGAUGGGCUCUGUCUUCGGGGGGCUGCAGGGGCCUGCUUUCCUCACGAGUUCCACCUGCAGAGGCCCAGGCAUUAUCCACGCUGCGGGAAGAGGCAGUAGCCACAAGCAGAACACAGCCCCCCUCCUGGAGCCCAUGGCCCAGGUGGUAAGGGGUGGCCGGUGUGGGGGGUCCCCUGGAGCAGCUGGGCCCAGUCCCUGUGAGCGCUGCUGUCAGCCUGAAGGUGGUGAGGGGAGGGAGCCCCGGGAGUACCUGGAAGACGCGUGCCCCAGGCAUGAGGCCCCCUCGGGGCCCCACCGGCCCCAUGCCCAGGUGCCCCAGGUGCCAGUGUGACUGGGCAGUCUCCCUUGGCUGCCCCGUGUUCACUCAGCUGGUGGAGCAGAUGAGUCUCUGAGCAUCUUGGGGUUGGCAGCGGUCGCAACUUGUGAUCACAGAACACAGAUUCCGAGAAGCACUUGAGAUUCUGUUCAGGUUUUCAAAGACGCGUGUGUGCGUGCCCUGGCGGCGCAGCAGAUCCCACUUCUGACCGAGGCAGGGUGUGUGUUUACACAGAUGAGCCUGGGCAGAGGGAGCCCAGAGGCCCUGGCAUGGCGCCCCCCUCCUUCCAGCACACGGAGAAGGCCUCCAUCCCUCAUAUGCCACGCUGUGACACGGUUUGGGACUGGCAGAAGAUUUAGGGCCCAGUGCACAGGCUCCUGGGCAGGCGGGAAACCAUCUCCCGAAAGCAGAAAACGUUGGCCACACGGUGGCAGCAGUCCCUCAGGCGUCCUGGUCGUUUCUGGUUGUCGCAAGUGGACUCCUCUUCCUUUGGGAGGCUGGAUCUGUCUUCCUCCUCUCACUGUGAGCAGAGGGAGGGAGAGCUAGCAGAGCCUGAGCUAGGGCCGGGAUCUAAUGACCGCCCUCUGCCUGUCCUUGGGCCCUGAAACCAGGGGCUCUUCACACACAUGCAGCUGUGAUUUCAGAGCCGGUCUCACUUCCUAUUGGCGGUGCCGGGCCAGGACAGAGUUGGACAGAGCUGUGGAAAAUGGGUCUCCAAUACUAUCUUGUUUUGAUUCCAGCGUUCCAUCAGCUGCCUUCAUGACACUUGUACAGCCGCAUUCUGAGCUCAACCCUGACCUUGCAGCUCUGUUUUUCCUUUUUGGUUACCUAUCUGUUUUUCAAGAACAACAUUGUGGAUAUAAAUAAAAUGCUAAGGGAAAUGAAA